AUUCAGGGGUGUACCAGGCCCCAGAGGCAGCGGAAAGGGAGACUGUGGGGAACUAGGAGCAACAGCAGGCAUGGACCAAAGCAGUGAAGGAUGUAUGAAAAAGAUUAGCAGUGUGAAUCUUGACAAACUUAUAAAUGACUUCUCACAGAUAGAAAAGAAAAUGGUAGAAACCAAUGGAAAGAACAAUAUACUGGAUAUUCAGUUGGAAAAAAGUAAUUGCCUAUUAAAAGUAAUGCAAGCAAAGGAGGUCUCCAUUAAAGAAGAAUGUGCUACUCUUCAUAAUAUAAUAAAAGGGCUACAACAGACCAUUGAAUAUCAACAGAAUUUGAAAGGUGAAAAUGAACAACUAAAAAUAAGUGCUGAUCUUAUAAAAGAGAAGUUAAAGUCUCAUGAACAGGAAUAUAAGAAUAAUAUUGCCAAACUUGUAAGUGAAAUGAAAAUCAAAGAGGAGGGAUAUAAGAAAGAAAUAAGCAAACUUUAUCAGGACAUGCAGAGAAAAGUUGAAUUAAAUGAAGAAAAGCACAAAGAACUAAUAGAGAAAAAGGAGAUGGAAAUUUCAGAGUUAAAUGCAAAGCUAAGAAGUCAAGAAAAAGAAAAACAAAAUGAAAUAAUCAAGCUACAACUAGAAUUUGAUGCCAAACUAGCAAGAGUUCAGACUAAAUCAAAAUCAUAUCAGGAUUCUACUGUUUUGCCACAAAGUAUCUACAGAAGGAAACUUCAGCAUUUUCAAGAAGAAAAAAACAAGGAGAUUGCAAUUCUUCGUAAUACCAUUCGCGAUUUAGAGCAACGCCUUUCUGUUGGCAAAGAUUCUCACCUUAAGCGUAGACGGUUUUGAGCUUAGCAGUAAAUUCAUUAGUUGGUAUUUAUUUAAAAGCAAUCGAAAGUUUCACUUCUGUUUUCAAUAUAUGCAUACAGCCUACAUAACAAACGAAGUCAGCUUUAAGGUUUUUAUUGAAUUUAUUUGGACAAAUCCGUACUGUAUCCAAUUCUGUACUGCAUUCUUGCUUAAUAGUAUUAACCAUAAAGGAGGUCAGGUUUAUAGGGUUUGGUUUACCUAUUAAACCAUCAUUGACUAUGGAAAUACUUACUAAGCAAUAUAGAGACAGACAAUAUUAUCUUUCCCCUUAUAUCUUUUAAGACAGCCACUCAAGUUUUAGAAGAGUAUGAUACAACAUUAGAGAAAGAAAGAUACAAAGGCUUUAUUCAUGUGUGAUAGUAAAAAUCAGGAUGAGUCUUAGAUAUACAAAAGAUAAAUGGAUAUUUAAAAUAGUUAUAUAUGCUUUUUUAGCAAAAUAUUCACGUGUUAAGUAUUUCUGGAUCUUAAAAUACAAAAUCCACUUAUUUUAUUAGUUAAAAGUAGAAGAUUGAAAAGACAAAGUAAUAUUGUUUUGAGAGAUAAGUAAAGAAAAAAAUGGAAAGCAUGUCUUUGUUGUUCUUCCUCCAUUCUAAACUGCUAAUUAUCCAACAGAAACCCCUAGGUCAUAGUUUACGUUUCUAUUCUCAUUAAAGCAAAUAGAACACUGGAAAAAGAAAAAAAAAGACAUAUUAACCAAAAGCUGCAAUCACCUUUCAGUUGCUCCAUCAUAAAAAAUAUGGUUUGAGUCAAUAUUUCUAUGACAUAAAAUUUAAAAUCUGGAAGCCAAUUCAGUAGAUUUCUCCAUGUUUGCACAAAUCUAAUUUCUAUUUUUGGUUCACUAAUUUGGUAGUUUAUAAAAAUGCUGGAAAUGAAAUUGUGUCUAGACUAAAUUGGGGAGUAUGUCCUAUUUUAAAUAUUUAGUUUGAAGGUCAUUCUCACUUUUUUGCCUGAUUCUUUCAGCGUCAACUGGCACUGGCUUCUGUGGGUAUAAGCUGCUGACUUAUUUGUCAGGCAGCUGGAGGCAAACGUCACUGACAAGAUUCAGUUAUGUUCUCCUCUGCCCGAAGUCCCUGUCAGCUACAUAAAGAUGGGAGGUUUUCUUUACACUGUCAGGUGAUUGCAGACCCUGUUUUUUCAAAUAUCAGAUGUCGACAAUGGCAGCAUCAGCUCCUAGGAGCCAACUCUGAAUCUGUGGGCAAUUUACAGAGUAAUUGAUUUAUACAUCUCUUUCGACAGAGCUUCUUUUGUAAAUCUUGUAAAUCUUCACUUGCUGGCAUAUCUCGGUUCUCUGGGUGACCCUGCCUAUGCUGACCCUUGUGCUUAUGGUGGUGAUGAAGGCCUGGAGGAGCAGGAUGAGUAGGAGCAUUUGGUGCUCCUGGUUGCUGAUUCUCUGAAAGCUCACUGCUGCCAAGGUGCUGAUGUCCAUGAUUGUGAUGAUGCUCAUGAUGGUAAUGAGGCGAUGGAGUUUCAACUGUUUUAUCCACAGUAGCCAAAGAUACACGUUUACAAAAGUCUUCAUCUUUGAGAGUCUGGAACAAAUUUAUAAAUCACUUUUUAACAAGCUUAUAGAGAUAGGAAUAAUGCGUGAAAAAUGAUUUGUAGAGCUAACAUGUGAAAUUCCAACUAGUUAAUUAGAAUCGAGCUGGCUUUGUAUUAUAUUAAUGAGAAAGAGUCUGAUGUUAGUCUCAACACCUAGACAUUUUAUUAAAGGCUUAAAAAGAAAGCCAAACCACUGUACUUAUAUUUGCAGAAGCAAAUGAAGUAAACUGGCAAAAGGAACUUGGAUUGCAGGAAAGUCAAAGUAAUAUCAAAUCCUAAAUUCAGUUGAUCUGGGCCGAGCAUGGUGGCUCAUGCCUGUAAUCCCACCACUUUGGGUGGCCGAGGGGGGCAGAUUACUUGGGCUCAGGAGUCGGAGACCAGCCUGGGCAACAUGGCGAGAUCCUGUCUCUGCAAAAUAUACAAAAAUUAGCUGGGUGUGGUGUCAGAUGCCUGUAGUCCCAGCUACUUGUGAGGCUGAGGUGGGAGGAUCGUUUGAGCCUGCAAGAUGGAGGUUGCAGUGAGCUCAGAUGGUGCCACUGCACUCCAGCCUGGGUGACAGAGUCAGACCCUAUCUCAAAAAAAUAAAAAAUAAAUAAAAAAUCAGUUGAACUAUAUGGAAACUUCUGUACCUGUGUCAACGGUGCAUCUUAUCUAAUACUAUAUGAUACUGUAAUCUAAUAUUAUCUCUGAUAAUUCAAAAAUGCUAAUAAACUCUGCUCAAAUGUGUUAGUUUUUCAUACUUCAUCCUAUGCCAGGAAAUGUUUUGAACUUCACCAAAGCUUUGCUAAUGUCUCCCUACCAUAAGGCUGUCAGCUGAAAAUAGCAAAUUACUGCCCGACUCCCAUUGACCAUAAUAUCCAUUCCGCAUGAUCCUAGUUCUUUAAUUUACUGGAAGUCUUUACUGUUUUGUGGUACCUACUAAUCAGAGACUCAAAGCCUAUAGAUACAGAAAUGUAACAGUAAAUCUCAACCUAAGGCUAAUUUGCAAAUAAAAUUACAAAAUCAACUUAGAACCCAAAGACUCACUAAGUGAUAUGCUUUUGAUGUUUUGAAGGUUUUAAAAGGUUAUAAAUUCCAUUAAAUUUUAGCAUACAACUA